ACUCGCGGCGCUGCUAACGGCCUGGUCACAUGCUCUCCGGAGAGCUACGGGAGGGCGCUGGGUAACCUCUAUCCGAGCCGCGGCCGCGAGGAGGAGGGAAAAGGCGAGCAAAAAGGAAGAGUGGGAGGAGGAGGGGAAGCGGCGAAGGAGGAAGAGGAGGAGGAGGAAGAGGGGAGCACAAAGGAUCCAGGUCUCCCGACGGGAGGUUAAUACCAAGAACCAUGUGUGCCGAGCGGCUGGGCCAGUUCAUGACCCUGGCUUUGGUGUUGGCCACCUUUGACCCGGCGCGGGGGACCGACGCCACCAACCCACCCGAGGGUCCCCAAGACAGGAGCUCCCAGCAGAAAGGCCGCCUGUCCCUGCAGAAUACAGCGGAGAUCCAGCACUGUUUGGUCAACGCUGGCGAUGUGGGGUGUGGCGUGUUUGAAUGUUUCGAGAACAACUCUUGUGAGAUUCGGGGCUUACAUGGGAUUUGCAUGACUUUUCUGCACAACGCUGGAAAAUUUGAUGCCCAGGGCAAGUCAUUCAUCAAAGACGCCUUGAAAUGUAAGGCCCACGCUCUGCGGCACAGGUUCGGCUGCAUAAGCCGGAAGUGCCCGGCCAUCAGGGAAAUGGUGUCCCAGUUGCAGCGGGAAUGCUACCUCAAGCACGACCUGUGCGCGGCUGCCCAGGAGAACACCCGGGUGAUAGUGGAGAUGAUCCAUUUCAAGGACUUGCUGCUGCACGAACCCUACGUGGACCUCGUGAACUUGCUGCUGACCUGUGGGGAGGAGGUGAAGGAGGCCAUCACCCACAGCGUGCAGGUUCAGUGUGAGCAGAACUGGGGAAGCCUGUGCUCCAUCUUGAGCUUCUGCACCUCGGCCAUCCAGAAGCCUCCCACGGCGCCCCCCGAGCGCCAGCCCCAGGUGGACAGAACCAAGCUCUCCAGGGCCCACCACGGGGAAGCAGGACAUCACCUCCCAGAGCCCAGCAGUAGGGAGACUGGCCGAGGUGCCAAGGGUGAGCGAGGUAGCAAGAGCCACCCAAACGCCCAUGCCCGAGGCAGAGUCGGGGGCCUUGGGGCUCAGGGACCUUCCGGAAGCAGCGAGUGGGAAGACGAACAGUCUGAGUAUUCUGAUAUCCGGAGGUGAAAUGAAAGGCCUGGCCACGAAAUCUUUCCUCCACGCCGUCCAUUUUCUUAUCUAUGGACAUUCCAAAACAUUUACCAUUAGAGAGGGGGGAUGUCACACGCAGGAUUCUGUGGGGACUGUGGACUUCAUCGAGGUGUGUGUUCGCGGAACGGACAGGUGAGAUGGAGACCCCUGGGGCCGUGGGGUCUCAGGGGUGCCUGGUGAAUUCUGCACUUACACGUACUCAAGGGAGCGCGCCCGCGUUAUCCUCGUACCUUUGUCUUCUUUCCAUCUGUGGAGUCAGUGGGUGUCGGCCGCUCUGUUGUGGGGGAGGUGAACCAGGGAGGGGCAGGGCAAGGCAGGGCCCCCAGAGCUGGGCCACACAGUGGGUGCUGGGCCUCGCCCCGAAGCUUCUGGUGCAGCAGCCUCUGGUGCUGUCUCCGCGGAAGUCAGGGCGGCUGGAUUCCAGGACAGGAGUGAAUGUAAAAAUAAAUAUCGCUUAGAAUGCAGGAGAAGGGUGGAGAGGAGGCAGGGGCCGAGGGGGUGCUUGGUGCCAAACUGAAAUUCAGUUUCUUGUGUGGGGCCUUGCGGUUCAGAGCUCUUGGCGAGGGUGGAGGGAGGAGUGUCAUUUCUAUGUGUAAUUUCUGAGCCAUUGUACUGUCUGGGCUGGGGGGGACACUGUCCAAGGGAGUGGCCCCUAUGAGUUUAUAUUUUAACCACUGCUUCAAAUCUCGAUUUCACUUUUUUUAUUUAUCCAGUUAUAUCUACAUAUCUGUCAUCUAAAUAAAUGGCUUUCAAACAAAGCAACUGGGUCAUUAAAACCAGCUCAAAGGGGGUUUAAAAAAAAAAAACCAGCCCAUCCUUUGAGGCUGAUUUUUCUUUUUUUUAAGUUCUAUUUUAAAAGCUAUCAAACAGCGACAUAGCCAUACAUCUGACUGCCUGACAUGGACUCCUGCCCACUUGGGGGAAACCUUAUACCCAGAGGAAAAUACACACCUGGGGAGUACAUUUGACAAAUUUCCCUUAGGAUUUCGUUAUCUCACCUUGACCCUCAGCCAAGAUUGGUAAAGCUGCGUCCUGGCGAUUCCAGGAGACCCAGCUGGAAACCUGGCUUCUCCAUGUGAGGGGAUGGGAAAGGAAAGAAGAGAAUGAAGACUACUUAGUAAUUCCCAUCAGGAAAUGCUGACCUUUUACAUAAAAUCAAGGAGACUGCUGAAAAUCUCUAAGGGACAGGAUUUUCCAGAUCCUAAUUGGAAAUUUAGCAAUAAGGAGAGGAGUCCAAGGGGACAAAUAAAGGCAGAGAGAAGAGACAGAACUAAAAAUACGAGGAAAGGAGAGUGAGGAUUUUCAUUAAAAGUCUCAGCAGUGGGUUUCUUGGGUUAUUUAAAACAUCACCUAAAUAGGCCUUUUCUUCCUAAUUGGCCAUCAAAUUAAAGCCUAUCCUUUCUCAAGCAGGAGCUGGUAUUGUAGGGAGUGGCCGGGUAUUCUGGGCUGGGCUCUUCUGGAGUAGGGGGUCAGCAAACAUUGUCUGCAAAGGGCCAGAUACUGAAUCCAGUACUUUCAGUUUGGCGAGCCGUGAGGUCUCUGUCGAAACUACUCAACUCUGCCGUCCUAGCACAAAAGCAGCCAUAGACAACACACAAACGAGAGGGCUUGGCUCCCUUCCAGGAAGAUUUAUUUAACAGGCUCCCAGCUGAAUUUCACUCACAGGACACAGUUUACUGAUCUCUGUUCUAGUGAGUGGGUCAAAAAGCAUAUGCAUCCUUAUCCGUCAACUCAUCAGCUCUUCCUCAAGGCAACCUGAGGCCAGACACCAAGAAACCAAGCGUAUCUGCUCUAAAAUGACUUGUUCCUGGGGAAUGCCUUCAACCAAAACACAGCUAGUAUUUCUAUGCCCCAAAUCCAAUCCCAGUCUUUCAUGAUCCAUGCCGGCGGUUGGGUGGGGAGGGGAAUCAUUGGUUGGGGGAAGGGAGGAAACCCCACCUCCAGCCCCCGCCACCGGGCUCCCUGGGCACCCAGCAAGAUCUGGGGCUGCAGAGAACAGAAGAGCUGGUGCACUUAAUCCAGCUCUGCCCUUGGGGGGAGGAGGACCUGUGUGUCAGGCUCUGCCAUGGGAACGAGUGUAAACCGUGGCUGUCUCCUGCAGUGAGCCACCGCGGCAGGCACGUUGACUGUUUUACUGACAUCACUCAAAAGCUAAAGCAAUAACAUUCUCCUGCGUUGCUGAGUCAGCUGUUCAUUUGUCCGCCAGCUCCUGGACUGGAUGUGUGAAAGGCAUCACAUUUCCAUUUUCCUCCGUGUAAAUGUUUUAUGUGUUCGCCUACUGAUCCCAUUCGUUGCUUCUAUUGUAAAUAUUUGUCAUUUGUAUUUAUUAUCUCUGUGUUUUCCCCCUAAGGCAUAAAAUGGUUUACUGUGUUCAUUUGAACCCAUUUACUGAUCUCUGUUGUAUAUUUUUCAUGCCACUGCUUUGUUUUCUCCUCAGAAGUCGGGUAGAUAGCAUUUCUAUCCCAUCCCUCACGUUAUUGGAAGCAUGCAACAGUAUUUAUUGCUCAGGGUCUUCUGCUUAAAACUGAGGAAGGUCCACAUUCCUGCAAGCAUUGAUUGAGACAUUUGCACAAUCUAAAAUGUAAGCAAAGUAGUCAUUAAAAAUACACCCUCUACUUGGGCUUUAUACUGCAUACAAAUUUACUCAUGAGCCUUCCUUUGAGGAAGGAUGUGGAUCUCCAAAUAAAGAUUUAGUGUUUAUUUUGAGCUCUGCAUCUUAACAAGAUGAUCUGAACACCUCUCCUUUGUAUCAAUAAAUAGCCCUGUUAUUCUGAAGUGAGAGGACCAAGUAUAGUAAAAUGCUGACAUCUAAAACUAAAUAAAUAGAAAACACCAGGCCAGAACUAUAGUCAUACUCACACAAAGGGAGAAAUUUAAACUCGAACCAAGCAAAAGGCUUCACGGAAAUAGCAUGGAAAAACAAUGCUUCCAGUGGCCACUUCCUAAGGAGGAACAACCCCGUCUGAUCUCAGAAUUGGCACCACGUGAGCUUGCUAAGUGAUAAUAUCUGUUUCUACUACGGAUUUAGGCAACAGGACCUGUACAUUGUCACAUUGCAUUAUUUUUCUUCAAGCGUUAAUAAAAGUUUUAAAUAAAUGGC